AGAUUGUGCCACUGCACUGCAGUCUGGGUGAGAGAGUGAGACCCUGUCUCAACAAACAAACACCCGCUGCUCUGAAUGAACGCUGUUGUGAAGAUGUCAGUGUGUGAGGAUGUUCACAGUCGUGCAGGAACGUUCUUGGGUGCCUCCCUGAUGCACACCUGGUGCAGCUGGGAGCUUCCCCACUGUGGAGGGGCUCCUGGUAGGAGGCAUUGUGAGCCCGUGCGGGAACGAAGGGCCCACCAUGCCUGCUCACAGUGGGCACACACACAUGCACACGCCCAUGGAGGAAGGUGGGAAGAAAUGUACAUGACAGUCACACGCAGAGGAGACACAUGUGGACUCACACCCAGGCUCUCAGCCUCUCUCCCUGCCUGCAUCCCCGACUUCCCUCCCUCCUAAAACUGGCAUGAGUUUGGAAUGUGUAAUAACAGCCUUUAGGGCAAAUUAGAACAGGGAGUAAACUCUUUCUCUGACCACAGAGAACAGGACAGUGUUUGGGGAGGGAAUUGCCACAGAGCAGCAGAGCCGGGUGUGUGUGUGUGUGUGUACACAUGCCUAUGUGUAUGUGUACACGUGAGCUAGUGUGUACACACUCCUGAGUGCUGUGAUGUGGAAGGAGCCCAGGGCUAGGAGUCUAGAGGUUUUCUUCAAAGCCAUUUGCUCCCUAGCUGGCCUCUCAGAGCCUCCGUUUCCUUAGCUGUAAAGUGGGAGCAAUAGCCUAGCUUUGUUCAGGUUCUUCGGGGGAUUGAAUGAGAGAGGGGCUUGGUGGAUUUUAGCAUGGGCUAUAAAAUGUCAGGCUGUAGUGCUGGCACGUGUGUGCAUGUGUGUUUUGGGGAAGGGGAGUAAGGAGGACAGGUAAAUCAGGACCAUAUCAUAGUGGUGAUGAUGAUAAUUAAAUGUGACAAGAUCCAACAUUUAUCAAAUAUUUCUUAGGUGCCCAAGAAACACUUGACCUGCCUUAUCUCCCAGAAGCCCUACAAGGGAGGUGCUAUUAUUGCAAUCCCCAUUUUACAAGUAGAGAAACCGAGGCUCAGAGAGAUGAGAAUGGGCGGCAGUAAUCAUCCCUUCCUCCUGGGGGUGGUUGUGAAGCUUGAAGGAGACACUGUAAGCGCUCGGGUGGUACCCUGGUACUCCAUCACUAACCUGCUGUGUGACCUCAGGCUGAGCAGUGCAGACGGGCCUGGGGCAGGCAUGGCGGAUUCCAGCGAAGGCCCCCGCGCGGGGCCCGGGGAGGUGGCUGAGCUCCCCGGGGAUGAGAGUGGCACCCCAGGUGGGGAGGCUUUUCCUCUCUCCUCCCUGGCCAAUCUGUUUGAGGGGGAGGAUGGCUCCCUUUCGCCCUCACCGGCUGAUGCCAGUCGCCCUGCUGGCCCAGGCGAUGGGCGACCAAAUCUGCGCAUGAAGUUCCAGGGCGCCUUCCGCAAGGGGGUGCCCAACCCCAUCGAUCUGCUGGAGUCCACCCUAUAUGAGUCCUCGGUGGUGCCUGGGCCCAAGAAAGCACCCAUGGACUCACUGUUUGACUACGGCACCUAUCGUCACCACUCCAGUGACAACAAGAGGUGGAGGAAGAAGAUCAUAGAGAAGCAGCCGCAGAGCCCCAAAGCCCCUGCCCCUCAGCCGCCCCCCAUCCUCAAAGUCUUCAACCGGCCUAUCCUCUUUGACAUCGUGUCCCGGGGCUCCACUGCUGACCUGGACGGGCUGCUCCCAUUCUUGCUGACCCACAAGAAACGCCUAACUGAUGAGGAGUUUCGAGAGCCAUCUACGGGGAAGACCUGCCUGCCCAAGGCCUUGCUGAACCUGAGCAAUGGCCGCAACGACACCAUCCCUGUGCUGCUGGACAUCGCGGAGCGCACCGGCAACAUGAGGGAGUUCAUUAACUCGCCCUUCCGUGACAUCUACUAUCGAGGUCAGACAGCCCUGCACAUCGCCAUUGAGCGUCGCUGCAAACACUACGUGGAACUUCUCGUGGCCCAGGGAGCUGAUGUCCACGCCCAGGCCCGUGGGCGCUUCUUCCAGCCCAAGGAUGAGGGGGGCUACUUCUACUUUGGGGAGCUGCCCCUGUCGCUGGCUGCCUGCACCAACCAGCCCCACAUUGUCAACUACCUGACGGAGAACCCCCACAAGAAGGCGGACAUGCGGCGCCAGGACUCGCGAGGCAACACAGUGCUGCAUGCGCUGGUGGCCAUUGCUGACAACACCCGUGAGAACACCAAGUUUGUUACCAAGAUGUACGACCUGCUGCUGCUCAAGUGUGCCCGCCUCUUCCCCGACAGCAACCUGGAGGCCGUGCUCAACAACGACGGCCUCUCGCCCCUCAUGAUGGCUGCCAAGACGGGCAAGAUUGGGAUCUUUCAGCACAUCAUCCGGCGGGAGGUGACGGAUGAGGACACACGGCACCUGUCCCGCAAGUUCAAGGACUGGGCCUAUGGGCCAGUGUAUUCCUCGCUUUAUGACCUCUCCUCCCUGGACACGUGUGGGGAAGAGGCCUCCGUGCUGGAGAUCCUGGUGUACAACAGCAAGAUUGAGAACCGCCACGAGAUGCUGGCUGUGGAGCCCAUCAAUGAACUGCUGCGGGACAAGUGGCGCAAGUUCGGGGCCGUCUCCUUCUACAUCAACGUGGUCUCCUACCUGUGUGCCAUGGUCAUCUUCACUCUCACCGCCUACUACCAGCCGCUGGAGGGCACACCGCCGUACCCUUACCGCACCACGGUGGACUACCUGCGGCUGGCUGGCGAGGUCAUUACGCUCUUCACUGGGGUCCUGUUCUUCUUCACCAACAUCAAAGACUUGUUCAUGAAGAAAUGCCCUGGAGUGAAUUCUCUCUUCAUUGAUGGCUCCUUCCAGCUGCUCUACUUCAUCUACUCUGUCCUGGUGAUCGUCUCAGCAGCCCUCUACCUGGCAGGGAUCGAGGCCUACCUGGCCGUGAUGGUCUUUGCCCUGGUCCUGGGCUGGAUGAAUGCCCUUUACUUCACCCGUGGGCUGAAGCUGACGGGGACCUAUAGCAUCAUGAUCCAGAAGAUUCUCUUCAAGGACCUUUUCCGAUUCCUGCUCGUCUACUUGCUCUUCAUGAUCGGCUACGCUUCAGCCCUGGUCUCCCUCCUGAACCCGUGUGCCAACAUGAAGGUGUGCAAUGAGGACCAGACCAACUGCACAGUGCCCACUUACCCCUCGUGCCGUGACAGCGAGACCUUCAGCACCUUCCUCCUGGACCUGUUUAAGCUGACCAUCGGCAUGGGCGACCUGGAGAUGCUGAGCAGCACCAAGUACCCCGUGGUCUUCAUCAUCCUGCUGGUGACCUACAUCAUCCUCACCUUUGUGCUGCUCCUCAACAUGCUCAUUGCCCUCAUGGGCGAGACAGUGGGCCAGGUCUCCAAGGAGAGCAAGCACAUCUGGAAGCUGCAGUGGGCCACCACCAUCCUGGACAUUGAGCGCUCCUUCCCCGUAUUCCUGAGGAAGGCCUUCCGCUCUGGGGAGAUGGUCACCGUGGGCAAGAGCUCGGACGGCACUCCUGACCGCAGGUGGUGCUUCAGGGUGGAUGAGGUGAACUGGUCUCACUGGAACCAGAACUUGGGCAUCAUCAACGAGGACCCGGGCAAGAAUGAGACCUACCAGUAUUAUGGCUUCUCGCAUACCGUGGGCCGCCUCCGCAGGGAUCGCUGGUCCUCGGUGGUACCCCGCGUGGUGGAACUGAACAAGAACUCGAACCCGGACGAGGUGGUGGUGCCUCUGGACAGCAUGGGGAACCCCCGCUGCGAUGGCCACCAGCAGGGUUACCCCCGCAAGUGGAGGACUGAUGACGCCCCGCUCUAGGGACUGCAGCCCAGCCCCAGCUUCUCUGCCCACUCAUUUCUAGUCCAGCCGCAUUUCAGCAGUGCCUUCUGGGGUGUCCCCCCACACCCUGCUUUGGCCCCAGAGGCGAGGGACCAGUGGAGGUGCCAGGGAGGCCCCAGGACCCUGUGGUCCCCUGGCUCUGCCUCCCCACCCUGGGGUGGGGGCUCCCGGCCACCUGUCUUGCUCCUAUGGAGUCACAUAAGCCAACGCCAGAGCCCCUCCACCUCAGGCCCCAGCCCCUGCCUCUCCAUUAUUUAUUUGCUCUGCUCUCAGGAAGCGACGUGACCCCUGCCCCAGCUGGAACCUGGCAGAGGCCUUAGGACCCCGUUCCAAGUGCACUGCCCGGCCAAGCCCCAGCCUCAGCCUGCGCCUGAGCUGCAUGCGCCACCAUUUUUGGCAGCGUGGCAGCUUUGCAAGGGGCUGGGGCCCUCGGCGUGGGGCCAUGCCUUCUGUGUGUUCUGUAGUGUCUGGGAUUUGCCGGUGCUCAAUAAAUGUUUAUUCAUUGACGGUGGA